CGCUGACCUGUCGGACUUCAACGGCCACAGCCACUGCACCCACUACCUGCGCACGGUGGAGAACCUGAGCAUGGAGCACUGCGUGCUCUCCCGGGAUCCAUCCGUGGAGCUGGAGGCGAAGCAGCCGGAUUCAGGCAUGUCCUCACCCAACACCACGGUGUCGGUCCAGCCUCUGAACUUUGACCUCAGCUCGCCCACCAGCACCCUCUCCAACUACGACUCCUGCUCCUCCAGCCACUCCAGCAUCAAGGGCCAGCACCCUCCACGUGGGCUUCCCAGCACUAGAGCUGCAGACAUACAGAGCUACAUGGACAUGCUGAACCCAGAGCUGGGCCUGCCUUGGGGCACGAUUGGGAAGCCCAUACCCCCACCACCCCCACCCAGCUUCCCCCCGCCACCCCCGCCCCCAGGCACCCAACUGCCCCCACCCCCACCUAGCUACCCAUCUCCCAAGCCUCCUGUGGGACCACAGGCAGCUGACAUCUACAUGCAGACCAAGAACAAACUCCGCCACGUGGAGACAGAGGCCCUCAAGAAGGAGCCGAGCUCCUGCGACGGCCACGACGGGCUACGGAGGCAGGACUCCAGCCGCAAGCCCCGCGCUUUCAGCAAGCAGCCCAGCACGGGGGACUACUACCGGCAGCUGGGCCGCUGCCCCGGCGAGACGCUGGUCGCACGCCCGGGCAUGGCGCACCGCGAGGAGGCGGAACUCCCUGGGAACCACGUGCCUAAUGGCUGCGCCGCGGACCCCAAGGCGUCCAGGGAGCAGCAGCUGCUGCCGCCGCCGCCGCCGCCGCCGCCCCUGCCCGAGGCCGCGAGUUCGCCGCCGCUGGUCCCGCCUCUGCCCCUCGAGGGCGCUGGCCCUGGCUGCGGGCAGCGCCGCUCCUCCUCGCCCACCGGCAGCACCAAGUCUUUCAAUGUGAUGUUCCCGAUGGGCGACAACUCAGAGCUACUGGCUGAGAUUAAGGCAGGCAAGAGCCUGAAGCCGACGCCACAGAGCAAGGGGCUGACCACAGUGUUCUCAGGCAGCAGGCAGCCGGCCUUCCAGCCCGAUUCGCCGCUGCCGUCUGUGUCACCUGCACUGUUACCAGUCCAGAGCCCCACACCGCCAGCUGCGGGGUUUCAGCUGCUGCUCAACGGAAGCUUGGUUCCGGUGCCGCCCACUACUCCUGCGCCGGGGGUGCAGCUGGACGUGGAGGCGCUCAUCCCCACGCACGAUGAGCAGGGCCGUCCCAAGCCCGAGUGGAAGCGCCAGGAGGAGGAGGAGGCCCGGCUGGCCAGCAUGCCCGCCUGGAGGUGGGACCUCCUGCGGAAGAAGCUGGAAGAAGAGAGGAAGCAGAAGCGCUCAUCACAGGUGUCUGUUCCUGGACCUCAGAUGGGUUAUUGGGAUCCUGUUUAGGGGAGGAGCCAUGCUGAAGAUUCAGUAAAAUGGGGAAUACAGGGGAUUCUGAGAGAAUCGAUGGCACAGAAUGUGAGGGGAGAUGAGUGGAGGGUUCCACCCCUUCUCUUGUUGACCACUGAGAAAACGUUUCCUAAGAGCUCCUCUGUAGACUUGAUUGGCGCUGUGCUGUGUGCUGUGGAUACAGAUAUGAGGAAAACAUUAUCCCAGCACUCCAGGAGCUCCAUCCGGAAAGCAAGUCACUGCCAAAAGGCAUGAGAAGUGCUGUGACAGACUUGAGUAAAGUCCACGGGGUUCACAACGGGCCAUGGUCAUCACUGCAUGGGGGUGGCCUCGGACUGUCCUGAUCCUUGUCUUGGCCCCUUUCACAGUUGGAGAACCAGUCCCAGCCUUGUGACACUGGGCCCAAUCAGCAUUUAGCCCACCAGGGUCCACCCA